GAGGGAGGACCUGCUGGCUGCAGUGAGGAGCGGAGGCGGGCGCGGGCGGCCGGCCAUGAUCGCGUCGUGCUUGUGUUACCUGCUGCUGCCGGCCACGCGCCUCUUCCGCGCCCUCUCAGAUGCUUUCUUCACAUGUCGAAAAAAUGUCCUUCUGGCGAACAGCUCAUCCCCCCAGGUAGAGGGCGACUUUGCCAUGGCCCCUCGGGGCCCUGAGCAGGAGGAAUGUGAGGGCCUGCUGCAGCAGUGGCGAGAAGAAGGGUUGAGCCAGGUGCUCUCAACUGCAAGUGAGGGGCCCCUUAUAGAUAAAGGACUAGCCCAGAGCAGCCUGGCACUUCUGAUGGAUAAUCCUGGAGAAGAGAAUGCUGCUUCAGAGGACAGGUGGUCCAGCAGGCAGCUGAGUGACCUUCGGGCUGCAGAGAACCUGGAUGAGCCUUUCCCUGAGAUGCUAGGAGAGGAGCCACUGCUGGAGGUGGAGGGGGUGGAGGGCUCCAUGUGGGCAGCUAUCCCCAUGCAGUCGGAGCCCCAGUAUGCAGACUGUGCUGCCCUCCCAGUGGGUGCCCUGGCCACAGAGCAGUGGGAAGAGGACCCAGCGGUGUUGGCCUGGAGCAUAGCACCUGAGCCUGUGCCCCAGGAAGAGGCUUCCAUCUGGCCCUUUGAGGGCCUGGGGCAGUUGCAGCCUCCCGCAGUGGAAAUACCAUAUCAUGAAAUUUUGUGGCGAGAAUGGGAGGAUUUCUCCACCCAGCCAGAUGCUCAGGGCCUGAAGGCAGGAGAUGGCCCUCAGUUCCAGUUCACUCUGAUGUCUUAUAACAUCCUGGCUCAGGACCUGAUGCAGCAGAGCUCAGAGCUCUAUCUACAUUGCCAUCCAGACAUCCUCAAUUGGAACUAUCGCUUCGUGAACCUCAUGCAGGAAUUCCAGCACUGGGACCCUGAUAUCCUGUGUCUCCAGGAAGUCCAGGAAGAUCAUUACUGGGAGCAGCUGGAACCCUCUCUGCGAAUGAUGGGCUUUACCUGUUUCUACAAGAGGAGGACUGGGUGUAAAACCGAUGGCUGUGCUGUCUGCUACAAGCCUACCAGAUUCCGCCUGCUCUGUGCUAGCCCUGUGGAGUACUUCCGGCCUGGCUUGGAGCUACUUAAUCGGGAUAAUGUGGGCUUAGUGUUGCUACUGCAACCACUCGUCCCAGAAGGCCUGGGACAAGUCUCGGUGGCCCCGCUGUGUGUGGCAAAUACCCAUAUCCUUUACAACCCACGCCGGGGCGAUGUCAAGCUGGCCCAGAUGGCCAUUCUCCUGGCGGAAGUGGACAAGGUGGCCAGACUGUCAGAUGGCAGCCACUGCCCCAUCAUCUUGUGCGGGGACCUAAAUUCUGUCCCUGAUUCACCUCUCUACAACUUCAUCAGGGAUGGAGAGCUCCAGUACCAUGGGAUGCCAGCCUGGAAGAGUCUCGCUCUGUUGCCCAGGCUGGAGUGCAAUGGCACGAUCUCGGCUCACUGCAACCUCUGCCUCCUGGGUUCAUGUGAUUCUCCUGCCUCAGCCUCCCAAGUAGCUGGGAUUACAGGCUGCUCAUUGGCUUUGACCGAGGAUGGUGACGUAGAUACGGUAUCUGGACAGGAAGACUUCUCCCAUCAGCUUUACCAGAGGAAGCUGCAGGCCCCACUGUGGCCCAGCUCCCUGGGCAUCACUGAUUGCUGUCAGUAUGUCACCUCCUGUCACCCCAAGAGAUCAGAGAGACGCAAGUAUGGCCGAGACUUCCUGCUACGUUUCCGCUUCUGCAGCAUCGCUUGUCAGCGACCAGUAGGACUGGUCCUUAUGGAAGGAGUGACAGAUACUAAGCCAGAGCGACCUGCGGGUUGGGCUGAGUCUGUCCUUGAGGAAGAUGCAUCGGAGCUUGAGCCUGCCUUCUCCAGGACUGUAGGUACCAUCCAGCACUGCCUCCACCUGACGUCAGUAUAUACCCACUUCCUGCCCCAGCGUGGCCGCCCAGAGGUCACUACAAUGCCAUUGGGUCUUGGAAUGACAGUAGAUUACAUCUUCUUCUCAGCUGAGUCCUGUGAGAAUGGGAACAGAACUGAUCACAGGCUGUAUCGAGAUGGAACUCUCAAGCUCCUGGGUCGUCUCUCCCUUCUCUCUGAAGAGAUACUCUGGGCUGCCAAUGGCUUACCCAACCCCUUCUGCUCUUCAGACCACCUCUGCCUGCUAGCCAGCUUCGGGAUGGAAGUCACCGCCCCAUGACAGGGCUCCCAGGGGAAGAGAGCUUCUCUUCCAGAAGAGCUCACUGGAUCAGAGACUGUGGAAAAAUCCCAUGCAUCUAGAAACUUAGAUCCAAGAAACUUACAUCCCCUCCCUUCCCCCUCCUCGUUCCCUUUUUCCCACGGUUAGACUUUCUCCAGGCCUGGCUGCGUUCUCUGCCUGUGGUCCUUGCCCCACCCCAGCCUCUUCCUAAUCCUGUGCCACACACUCAGUGGCCCUGGGAGAGGCAGAAGGGGGGCUCCCCCUUCCUUCCAUGUAUCCAGCGCUCCCCCUUGAUUUUUAAUUACCAGGGUUAUGGGAGUUCUUGAUUUCAUUGGUUAUUUGCUUUCAGGCCGUUUCUUGAUGUACCUUCUGACCUGACCUUUUCCCUGCCUUCAGGACUUCUGGGCCCAGCCCUCUUGCCAGGCAUGCAUAUGUGAGAUAUGCAUAUCAUGUAUGUGUCCUCUUGGGGUGAGACUUCUGCACAGCCAUGCCUGCCUCUGACCAGUCCACUUUUCAUGUUGGGGCUGUAGGCCUGGGGCAGGUUCAGAGUCUACCCAAGUACCUAUGUAUGAGCAGGCAGCAGCAGGGCAUGGCCCCAUCUCUCCUUUUAGCCUCUGUGUUUCAUUAGGCAUUCAUCCUGCCAACCAGGGCAGGCCCGGCGUCUGGGCUCUGGGAACAAAUGGGGCCCACAUCCUGGAGUGGCAAAUUUUGGGGGAUGCGCUACCUGUCCCAGCUGGCCCUGUGCCUCCAACCCAGAGCUCCCCACAGACCUGGUGUAAUUUCACAAGGGCCAUCCCUUUCCCCAGGCUUCCCUGAGGGAGGCGGAAGUUUGAACCCUUAUGUGGGGUUCAUUGGGCUAGGGUAGUGGUAUGAGGUUUAAAACUAUUUAAGGAUUAGGAGGAGAAAGAGUCUUCAGGAAACUCUUGUUUCACUGGACUCUGCAGCCUGCAGAACUGGGGCAAGGGUAGGAGUUCCAGUAGGGGAAGGAGCAGGUAGACUCUUCAGCUGCCUCAGCUGGGACUGAAGACCUAAGCUGAUUCUCUUUCCUCUCCACUCCUAAGAAGCAAUUUUCUGUUCCUCUCCUUCCACCACUUUUUACUUUCUGCUAUCUCCCAUCUCCCGCUUCCCUUCCAUUUCCUUUCUAGAAAACCCUGGUAUUUAGCUCAGGCCAAACUGCCUCAGCAGAAAGGUGGCCUUGGACAAAACUGGUCCAAGAAUUUGAAGUGGCAGUACUUGCGGAUUGGCUCUGUCCAGCAAGGCCUCAGCUGCUUGUUGCGUCUGCUUUCCCUCCCCUAACAGAAGGGUACCCUGGCUUAUUCAGGGGACUCCUUAGUCCACACUGUGUCACCUGCAUGCCUUAAUCUUUCAUUGCUGGGGUGUGGCCUUGGGAGAUCCUGGGCCAGCCCCUCCACACAUCUCCCUAAGUCAGAGUGGCUGCUGGCCCUGGUAGAUUUGACUUGCUCUUGCCUCACUCGACCUCCAAAGUGGGACUGAAGACAGUGGUCAAGAGACUUGAGUUCGGGACAGUAAGCCAGGGGUUAAGGUUCUUUCCUUUUUUUGAAAGCCAAAGACCCAGUUUGCAUUGUGCUGCUGCAUUCAUGGUUAGAAGCUUUCCAUGCCUAGGUUCUAGGGAAUUUAUUUUUCUAUGUGUAUAUAUUUUCAAACUUUGUUUCCUGGGUACUGGGCAUGUGCCUGUCUGAGCCCCAGGUCUGUCUACACCCCACCAUUCAUUCUGUCUGUCUGUUCCCUGGACACUGCCUAAAAGGGUCUCAAGACAGUGCCCUGUGGGUUCCUAGGACUAGGGCCCAUCACUGUUCUCUUCUGCUGGGAAAUGCAGCUUUAAAAUGGCUAACCACAGCAGAGGGCAGAUGCUUGAUAGAUUAUCUUUUCCUUGCUUUCUUGUUUCUGUUUUGAAAGUGAAAUGGGGUUUUAAAUUGUUAUUUAAACUCUUUUUCCAAAUAAAGGUUUACCUUUUUUCCCCCCAAUGUUGUUCAUUUUAUUAGGAUCCUGAAGGGAUUAGGUCCUUGAGAGAGGGCCUGAAGAAUGAGGUGGGCAGAGGAAGAGACUAAGGAGCUUUUGAUCUUGGGGUGGGGUCUCAAGACAUGAAUCUAGAUUGAGAAAUGUGUUGUAAGAUCUCCCUCUAUUAGCUGAGGUAAAUUCCCACUGCUGUGAGGCCUGGGAGGAACAGGGCUUGAGUGAAGCCUCCUGCCUUGACACUGCUGGGGUACAGCUUUCUUCUGUCCUUCCCAAGUGAGAGAAUGAUUCUUUGGACUGCUUUUCAUUCUUCCUCCAUCUGCUCCCCCCAUGCCUCCUCCUAGUAUCUUCUGCACUUCAGGAGGGUCUGUGCAAAGUGGGAUAAGAUGUGUGUUUUCCUGAUUAAAGCUAUGGCAGCUGCAUGAGACAUGAUGCGGGUGGCACAUGCCUCUUGCUGAGCAUCUAUUUCUGAUCUCUUUUGCAUUCUGGAGCCAGGGCUGAGCAGUGGGCCAUCUGUCGCUGGAAAAAUGUCUCUUCCUUCCUAGGCCUACCUCUGUUGGUGCUUUUGUCUUCCAACCUCCCUAUGUAGUAAGACCAGCCAAGCCCACAUGCCCACUGGGAGCCCUGAAACCAGAUCUGGUUUUCUGUCUUACCUGAACAGGUUCCCAGAACCCACACCAGGCCUCUGAAUCAGUCUCUGAGAAUCUGAUUGAUUUAAAGCCACUUGGUUGCUUCCAUUGCACUACCUGGGUUGCGAUCCCCUCAAUUGAUUUAGUAAAAAGAAAACUUAGCGGCCGGGUGCGGUGGCUCACACCUGUAAUCCCAGCACUUUGGGAGGCUGAGGCGGGUGGAUCACCUGAGGUCGAGAGUUCCAGACCAGCCUGACCAACAUGAAGAAAUCCCGUCUCUACUAAAAAUACAAAAUUAGCCGGGCGUGAUGGCGCAUGCCUGUAAUCCCAGCUACUUGGAGGCUGAGGCAGGAGAAUUGCUUGAACCUGGGAAGCGGAGGUUGUGGUGAGCCGAGAUCAUGCCAUUGCACUCCAGCCUGGACAACAAGAGUGAAACUCCAUCUCAAAAAAAAAAAAAGAAAAGAAAAGAAAAGAAAGAAAACUCAGCUAGGAAUUAGAAACAUCAUUUGUCCUCUUGGCCUGUUCAGCUGGUGACUGUAGGUAAGUUACUUAACCUCUCUGUAUUUCAGUUCACAUUCCUUGGUGAAAUAGAAAUUAAAGUUAAUAAUCACUUCUA